CGGGGACCAGCUCGGGGGUCCUGAUGGUGGGCCCCAACUUCCGCGUCGGCAAGAAGAUCGGCUGCGGCAACUUCGGGGAGCUCCGCCUAGUGCAGAGUAGAAGAGCCGGGAAGGACCCCAUCACCAUCAGAUGCAUCAGAGCUUCAAAGGCCCGCCCAUCAAGACGCUGCCAAGAGCAUGAGGCCAGCCAGGCUGGGGAGGACGUUGGCGAGCAUCCGCCUGCCCGUCAGGGAGCCACAGCUGGAUGAUACAUCGACAGACAGCAGAGGGACGGUGUAGCACACAGGCGAGGGCUUGUCCUCCUCAGCCUGGGGGAGCGCAGCUCAGUGCUUGGUGGUCAGCACGUGACUGACACUUUGCCGGAGAAGGGGACGGCUGCCCGCAGGAAGAGCUACACAGCCGUGUUCGCCGGAACUCCGCUCUGGAGAGUCAGAACUGGAGACGGGAGGGCGUGCCUCAAGGGCAGAUGGGCAAACCAAACCCCAUCCUCCCUGUGAGCCGCGGCACAGCACCAGGCGGGCACACGCAGCACGACACGGCGAGGAGCCCACCGCAGGGGCAGCCUUUUGGGCGGGGAAGGGGGGAUGAAUCCACUGUGAAUCCCACCUCCGAAGGGCAGCGCAGGAAGGACACGCAAAUGCUGGACUGAACCUGCAGCUGAUUCAGGGGGCAGUGUCCUGAGCUCUAAAACUUCAAACCUGGGGCAGUGUCCUGAGCUCUAAAACUUCGAAAUCUGACCAGGCACAGUGGCUCACGCCUGUAAUCCCAACACUUUGGGAGGCUGAUGUGGGCGGAUCACCUGACGUCAGGAGUUCGAGACCAGCCUGGACAACAUGGAGAAAGCCCAUCUCUAGUAAAAAUACAAAAAUUAGCCAGGUUGAUGGUGCCUGCCUGUAAUUCCAGCUACUCAGGAGGCUGAGGCAGGAGAAUCGCUUGAACCCAGGAGGCAGAGGUUCCAGUGAGCCGUGAUCGCGCCAGUGCACUCCAGCCUGGGCAACAGAACGAGACUCUGCUCCAAAAAGAAAAAAACUUUGAAAUCCCUCUAAAAAUAAAAUGGACCGGUGGAUGGUAGCUGUGAGGAUGGACCGUGUGGCAGGAAAGAAUCUCUAUACAAAUGAAUACGUGGCUAUCAAAUUGGAGCCGAUCAAGUCCCGGGCCCCGCAGCUGCACCUGGAGUACCGGUUCUACAAGCAGCUCAGCGCCACAGAGGGCGUCCCUCAGGUCUACUACUUCGGUCCGUGCGGGAAGUACAACGCCAUGGUGCUGGAGCUGCUGGGGCCCAGCCUGGAGGACCUGUUCGACCUGUGCGACCGGACCUUCACGCUCAAGACGGUGCUGAUGAUCGCCAUCCAGCUGAUCACGCGCAUGGAGUAUGUGCACACCAAGAGCCUAAUCUACCGGGACGUGAAGCCCGAGAACUUCCUGGUGGGCCGCCCGGGGACCAAGCGGCAGCAUGCCAUCCACAUCAUCGACUUCGGGCUGGCCAAGGAGUACAUCGACCCCGAGACCAAGAAGCACAUCCCGUACCGCGAGCACAAGAGCCUGACGGGCACGGCGCGCUACAUGAGCAUCAACACGCACCUGGGCAAGGAGCAGAGCCGCCGCGACGACCUGGAGGCGCUGGGCCACAUGUUCAUGUACUUCCUGCGCGGCAGCCUCCCCUGGCAGGGGCUCAAGGCCGACACGCUCAAGGAGCGGUACCAGAAGAUCGGGGACACCAAACGCGCCACGCCCAUCGAGGUGCUCUGCGAGAACUUCCCAGAGGAGAUGGCCACGUACCUGCGCUAUGUGCGGCGCCUGGACUUCUUCGAGAAGCCCGACUAUGACUACCUGCGGAAGCUCUUCACCGACCUCUUCGACCGCAGUGGCUUCGUGUUCGACUAUGAGUACGACUGGGCCGGGAAGCCCCUGCCGACCCCCAUCGGCACCGUCCACACCGACCUGCCCUCCCAGCCUCAGCUCCGGGACAAAACCCAGCCGCACAGCAAAAACCAGGUGAGGCCCGGGCGGGACCGACCGCCCCAGGGAGGGGCAUGGGCGGCCAGCGUGACCCCCUACUGCCCCCACCAGGCGUUGAACUCCACCAACGGGGAGCUGAAUGCGGACGACCCCACGGCCGGCCACUCCAACGCCCCGAUCACAGCGCCUGCAGAGGUGGAGGUGGCCGAUGAAACCAAAUGCUGCUGUUUCUUCAAGAGGAGAAAGAGAAAAUCGCUGCAGCGACACAAGUGACCCUGGGCGCGUGCAGCCCCCUGAAUCUUCUCCGUGCAGCCCCUUGGGGCGCGACCUUGUGCGAGGCCCUCGGGGCCCACCCACAGCGGCCCAGGGCCAGACCCUGGCUGGAAGCCAGAACGCAGACUGCAGGGGCCGCGCCUGGCUCAGGCGGCCCCACCCCCGGGACGUGGGGUCACUUCCUUCAUGUAAGACUUUGGCCGAAAUUUCUACACCUGUGUCUAGUCCUCCCCUCCAAGAGCAUUAACUAUUUAAAACAAGGAAAAGAGGAAAAAAAAAACAGAGGCCCGCCCUACCCCACUCCUGCCCCUCCGUUUCUUUGCUGAAGUGAGUAGUGUGAUCCUGGAGGCCCCCCGGCCUGGCCCCGCCCCGCCAGCCGCCCCCGUUAGCGUCAUAAAGUCCAGCUUGUCUCCCUCGAUCCAAAGGCCGUUUUCUCGAGGGGAGGGCAGGCCCGGCCUGGAGGGGUGCUGUGGAGCUGUCUUGCCCAGGCCCUCCUGGGAGGGGGACAGGCAUUGUUGCCAGGGGUGAGGCCGUGCCCCAGGCCUCCCCGAAACCAAAGGGGAAGGCAGGGGUGGGGCCGUGGCUGAAGCCGGCUCCCCAACCAAAAUGCUGCACCAAAGCUCGGGCGCCGCGGGCACGGCUGCUGCAGUCUCUUCCCAGCCUGGCCCUGGCAAGGGGCGGGUGGGCGCUGCCAGGCGGGUGCUUCUCGACGCACUUGCUCCCGGAGGCUGCGCCCCGGCGCCUGGAACCCGAGGUGGGAGGACCGGUUGGUGUCACCCUGCUCGGCCCUCAGCCCUGCCGCGUGGGGCGCGUGGGCACGGAGCUUCCUGCCUCUCUGCUCCGACACCCGGCAAGCAGCCGGAGACAAAACGCCUUAAAGCCCCCGGCCCAGCCCUGCAGGUAUAUUGCAGGGGCCUGGGGGCGGCCCUGGACUGGCGGGCGGUUCCCCAGUGGGGUGCCCUGGAGGCUGCCGGGCAGAGUGGAGCAGCUUGGGGCCGUGCCCAGGGCGGUGGCUGUGAGUCUAGUUUUUGCUUUACCAAGUGUACAGAAAUGGCAUUUACGUUUCUCUGAUGCUCCCUUGAAGCCAUAGAAUUUAGGGGCUUUUUUAAAAAAAUAAAAGAAAAAUGAAACCAAA